GGAGUGUUCAUUGCUAUUGGGGUAUCACUGCUCCUAGACUCUCUCAGUGGACAGAGCAAGGAUAUAUAUGCACACACACUAUUAGAUCAAUAUUUAUCUCUCUAUAUAGAAAACCAUGAGCUCACUUCAAUACUUUCAAUUCUAAUCAAAACCACAGGGCUUAUUCUGGGUUUCCCUCCUUCCAUAUUCAUGACUGCCUUCUCCAUGAGUGAGAAAACUGGCUCCCAACUUUGCUCAGUUGGUCCCCCUGCAUAUACCCAAUCUUCCAUAGCAGAACUCUGCCCCUCCACUCAUUCUGUGUGGCUCUGGCAUCCACACUUGGUUGUCCCCUUCUGCCAUGUGGACUUUCAUUUGACAGUACUUGGACUCUAACACCCUGUGCUAGGCCACCGUGCCCCUGCCUCCCUGCAUGGCCACUCUUUGUCCUAUUCUGGCUCUGACAUGCCAUGCCAGGCUCCCCCACGCCAGAUGGGUGCCAUCUGGUACAUAUCCCGUGUGCUUAGCUUAGACUACCCGGGCUAUGAUGGCUACUGUCCCACCCAUGCCCAUGUGCUGCAUGCAUCUUAUGAAGGCAUCUGGUUUAUUCUCCCUGCUCAUCAGUUCAAUCAGCAUGUGCUACCAGUGUAGUGCACCAGCAUACCAUCUGUGGAUCUGUGGGAUGUUCAGAAGAUCAAGGUCUCUGUAGACCACACUAUAACAGAAAGCUGGAAAACGAACAUGAUCUGGGAGAAGACACUGACUUUGUACUUCUAUCCUUGCCAGGUGAAAGCAAACUUCUGCUGGUUCUUACCGAUACAGAUGGGGAGAAAACACAAGCUGAGUCAAUAGCUACAUACUAAGUGCUGAGAGUGGUUAAGUUGUUCUAUGUUGCAUUUAGAAAAGCAGCUAAAAUUGGAGUUACUGCCUGAUUAAAUUUACGACGACAUACAGUCAUUCUCCAAGAUUCAGCAACUUCCUGCACAGGCUAAAGAGCUAAAGAGGUGAGCCAAGUGGGCAGAAAUGUGACAGGCCUCCCUGUCCCUGCAUCUUUCAUGUCUUUAAUCAUGGCAUCGAUCCCUGUAAUUCCCCUAGAAAUACAGUAAUGCAGGUUUACUAUUUGCGUAGGGAAAGAAAAUCCCAGGCUCCUGGGCCUGUUCAACCAUUUCUUUGACCUCAUCUCUCCUUGCUUGAUUUUAUACCAGUUGUGCUGGAGUACCUUCUAAUAUGGUUUGGCUCUGUGUCCCCACCCAAAUCUCAUCUCUAAUUGUCAUCUCCACAUGCCGAGGGAGGUACCUGGUGGGAGGUAAUCGGAUUAUGGGGGCAGUUUACCUCAUGCUGUUCUCAUGAUGGUAAGUUUCCACGAGAUCUGAUGGUUUAAAAGUGUUUGGGAGUCCCUAGCCUCUCUCCUGCCGCCAUGUAAGAUGUACCUUGCUUCCCCCUCUGCCAUGGUUGUAAGUUUUCUGAGGCCUCCCCAGCCAUGUGGAACUGCGAGUCAAUUAAAGCUGUUUUGUUUAUAAAUCACCCAGUCUUAGGUAGUUCUUUAUAGCAGUGUGAAAAUGGACUAAUACACUUCCUUAAUGAACUCUCUCAGAAAGGAUUCAGGAAAUGUAAGCUUGCAAGUUUAGAAAUAUCCUUAUUCUACCUUUACACUUGAUAUUAUCGCUGAGAUGAGCGUUUUAGGUUCAAAAUAUAUUUCCAGGAGUCCUAAAAAUAUAGCUCCAUCUUUUCAGAGUCUUCCAUCAUCCUAUGUUGUUGACAAGACUGAGAAUGGUCUCUGUCUCUCCUUUCCUUUGUAGGCAACCUUUCUCUUCCUGCUCCCACCCAUGGAACAUUUUAGAAUCUUCUUUUUUUUUUUUUUUUUUUUUUUUUUUGGUGUUUUGAAAUUUUGCAGUACCUGUCUAGGUGUGGAGCAGUUCCUCGGGCUUCCUUUUAAUCUGUAGCUCUGGAAUACUCUUGCUAUUGAUGAUUCUAUGUGUCGACUAUUUUGCUCACACCCCACCCAGAUGCAUUCUCUACUGUGGUUCUCUGCUCUUCCCUGUGCCAGGGGAAGCUGAUGGCUCCUUUGCUGGCAGGGCUCCAGUUGGGUUUGGUCAAUGGGAGGGACUGACAGGAGACUGGAAGUGGAAGGAGAGAGAGGUUGGUAGAAUUCUUUUCUACUUCCCCUUGCUUCCAUGCUGUCUGGAGGCGGUGGCAUGCCUCCACACUACAGAAGCUCCCACUGGGGGCCCUUCCUCUGCAGUCCUCUGGCUGUGAUGCUGUGUGUGGACUUGUGCUGGGAUCUGGAGGCGGAGACAAGAGCUGUGACCUAGACAUAGGGGAGUGGGGAGACAAAGCUGCUCAGGCAGACAACCAACUAGGCUGCUACAUCUGCCUCUGCAGCAGAGCAUGGGAGGGUGGUAGGAAUUUGUCAUGGCAGCAGGGACAUCGGAGCUGGGGUGCAACGGAGGAGCAGCCGCUUUCCAGGUAGUCAAGACAGGAAGGAGCAUGGUCCAGAAAGAAGAGAUGACAGGUGCCAGUCUACAGCGAUGGCGUCAUCCCUCAAGUGUAUCACUUAGUUCAAGAGUCCUGGAAUCUUUUCACAUCCACUAUGAACACCUCUCACCUCCUGGCCUUGCUGCUCCCAAAAUCUCCACAAGGUGAAAACAGAAGCAAACCCCUGGGCACCCCAUACAACUUCUCUGAACAUUGCCAGGAUUCCGUGGACGUGAUGGUCUUCAUUGUCACUUCCUACAGCAUUGAGACUGUCGUGGGGGUCCUGGGUAACCUCUGCCUGAUGUGUGUAACUGUGAGGCAGAAGGAGAAAGCCAACGUGACCAACCUGCUUAUCGCCAACCUGGCCUUCUCUGACUUCCUCAUGUGCCUCCUCUGCCAGCCGCUGACCGCCGUCUACACCAUCAUGGACUACUGGAUCUUUGGAGAGACCCUCUGCAAGAUGUCGGCCUUCAUCCAGUGCAUGUCGGUGACGGUCUCCAUCCUCUCGCUCGUCCUCGUGGCCCUGGAGAGGCAUCAGCUCAUCAUCAACCCAACAGGCUGGAAGCCCAGCAUCUCACAGGCCUACCUGGGGAUUGUGCUCAUCUGGGUCAUUGCCUGUGUCCUCUCCCUGCCCUUCCUGGCCAACAGCAUCCUGGAGAAUGUCUUCCACAAGAACCACUCCAAGGCUCUGGAGUUCCUGGCGGAUAAGGUGGUCUGUACCGAGUCCUGGCCACUGGCUCACCACCGCACCAUCUACACCACCUUCCUGCUCCUCUUCCAGUACUGCCUCCCACUGGGCUUCAUCUUGGUCUGUUAUGCACGCAUCUACCGGCGCCUGCAGAGGCAGGGGCGCGUGUUUCACAAGGGCACCUACAGCUUGCGAGCUGGGCACAUGAAGCAGGUCAAUGUGGUGCUGGUGGUGAUGGUGGUGGCCUUUGCCGUGCUCUGGCUGCCUCUGCAUGUGUUCAACAGCCUGGAAGACUGGCACCAUGAGGCCAUCCCCAUCUGCCAUGGGAACCUCAUCUUCUUAGUGUGCCACUUGCUUGCCAUGGCCUCCACCUGUGUCAACCCAUUCAUCUAUGGCUUUCUCAACACCAACUUCAAGAAGGAGAUCAAGGCCCUGGUGCUGACUUGCCAGCAGAGCGCCCCCCUGGAGGAGUCAGAGCAUCUGCCCCUGUCCACAGUACAUACGGAAGUCUCCAAAGGGUCCCUGAGGCUAAGUGGCAGGUCCAAUCCCAUUUAACCAGGUCUAGGUCUUCUCCCUGCCAUGUCCCUUGCCAGGCUCUUCCACUUAGCUAAGUGGGCACACUGCAAGCUGGGGUGGCACCCCAGCAUUCCUGGCUUUCUGGGGUCCAGAUAGGCUGGCAAGAGCUGUUUUUGCAUCCAUUUGCAUCGUGAAGACUGGCAUUUUGAUACUUCAGCUGUUUGUUCCUGGGAGAAUUCUGAGCACAGAUUCCAGAGGUCACAGUAAGCCUUGCAGCUUGAGCUGAAAGAUGCCAGAGCCGGAGAUGUCUGCUGGCAGCAGGCAGGGUUCAUUCUGGUGACACAGCAACAGAUGCCUGGCCUGGGAACCCAGGGAUUUCACCUCCACCAGUGAGACCACGGGGCCACUGUGGGGUGAGGGAAGGAGCGCUUGGAGUCAGAGCUCUAGA